UAUUUUUUUAUUUUAUUCUAUAAUUUGUGUAUUUUGUUAUAUAUUUUAGUUUACUUUAGUUUCAUAUAUUUACUUUAGUUUAAUAUAUUUUAGUUUAGUUUCACAUAUUUUGCAUUGUAUGGGAGGAAAAAAGAAUUCUCUCUCUAUUCUUCCGAAUUCUUAUCUGGAACCCCUGCAAAAAAAGGCAGAUGAAAAAGAAAAAAGCGAACAGAAGUUUAUUAACAAAUAGGCUUCACGUAUAUAUGGGAGAUACCCAGGGAAUGAGCAAUUCUCAAAGAAGUGGCUUAGAACUCUGGUUUAUGUGGCAUCAUCAACAAAGAACAACACAUUGGUGGGGAAGUAACAAGACAAGGGGAAAGGAUCUUGAGUUUCUAGGGGUGGCAAAUUGUGGGAAAACAAAUACAUGGGAAACUAAUGAUAGACAAAAGGUUAUAUAGUAAAGUCUGUUAUGUAGAUUUCCCUGUGCCAUCUUCAGGCAAGCAAGGGCCUAAGGUCAUCCCUGGUGAUCAACCUUUGUCCUUCUUGGUAGAGAGGGAAGGAGGGACACCUUUAUAAGUGUAUGUCCUGCUUUUAAGCAAAUAGGGGUAGGGCAGAGAGAUUUUUUGUAUCUACUUCUCGAUUGCUUUCAACCCAAAAUAAUCCUUAUGCCAGAGAGGCAUAUUUUGGGGUGGCAUAUUCAGCUACCCUUCAGCAAAAAGUAUCUACAUAUCUUGUACCAACUGGUCUCCUUCCCUGUUUGCAGCUGUACAAAUUAAGGUAUUAUGAAAGCAUGGUCAUUCAAAGGAGGCACCCGUUCUGCUGCUCCUUUGUAACUUUCUUUUGCCCGCCUGUUUUUCCUCUGCCCUCCUGUUUGCUGCUCCUUUGCAACUUUCACUCCAAGCUUUACAAACAUUUUUAGUGUCUUAAGUUUCCUCCUUCCCCACAACACACAAAUUCAUAUAGUCCAGCCCUGUGUAUUCUAUUUCCAGAGCCGGGGAUAGCUUCCCUUUUCUUCUUCUGCCAAAUCAUGUUUCUGCCUUAUUUUAAAAGUCUACUCAAAAUUCAUCUACAGCAAACCUUCUUAGAUGCAUUUUUUCUACAGGGAGAAUGCUCCAAUCACUCCAGUGAUUUCAUCAGCACACUUACUUGAUGUAAGCUCUUAUAUUUUCUCACAUUUGCAGUAUAUUCACCAUUAGGUUGUAAACUUUUGGAGGCAGCCAGUGUGUUCAUUUUUCCCUUAGGGCACCCUGCCCUUCUACAUAUAGUAGAAACUCAGGAAUUUGGUUAAGCAACUUUCUAUUUUCCCCAAACCUUAAAAGAGCUGUCUGCAAUGACCAUCUCAGACGUUGUUAGUUUCAGAAAGUUUCCCUAAUUUAUUUUAAGGAAAGAACAGAUAAGAUGCAUAAGAUAAGGGACAUUCUCUGGCUGUAGGCUUUCUUUAGCACAUUUCAGGAUUAUUAUAACAUAAAAGCCUUGCCCUAUUUUCCUUAAGCAGCACGCGGCUGCCUAGUGUACUUGCCUUAGGAGGUCAAACACAUUAGGUAUACCAACAUAUCGACCACCAAAAGCCAAUGCACAGAACAGAGGUCCUCGGGCAAACAGGUUGAACCAUAGUUGCAAGGUCAAGCCAUUAUAAUGCAAAGCAUCCAAGGGUGACCAUCAUGCUUUCCCCUGCGUUUCUGCAAAGCACAGAUUUUCCCAGGGAUUGCUGAGCAAAGAGCCCCUUACUAAAGAAACAGCAGACUCCAUGGAAGAGUGUCAAUUUUAUGAUCCACUGCUGGUUUGGGCUGAUUUGCUUUUAACUAAUUAUUGAUCACCGUAAUGACUAACUUUUGAGAGAGCCCUGCCAAAAAUAAAUAUUCCUUAAAUGAGGUACACCAAUGUUUUUUUCCACUCCAGUCCUUGAAAAUGGUGAGUUAGAGCAGAGUUUCCUAAAGCAUGGCCUGAAUUUACGGAACCAUGGUCAACAGAAUCACUUGGGCAAUUUGUUAAAAUGUAUUAGGUUGGUGCAAAAGUAAUCACGGUUUUUGCCAUUGAAAGUAAGGGUCCUAAUACAUUCCUGGGGCUCACCUGAGCCAGGAUUUCUGGCAUGGGGCCUAGAGAUCUGCAUUUAAACAAGAGCCACACAGAAGCACUUGGACAGAGGGUAAGAAGGGAAUGUGAUACUGAAGUCUCAAAAAUACAGAAGAAUAGUAAGGAAUGAUCUUCAUCAAUAUUAUCAUAGCUUUUUCUUGUUAGAUUAUAGGAUCCCAGGCUUAUGUCCUCAGAGAACAGAAUGGAGAGCAGAUUUAUAGACAGGGAAGGGGAUUGGACAGGACUGUGGGCCUGCAUUCUAUUUUAGGCCCUGCCUCUGAUUGUCUGUGUGGCUUUGAAGAGUUCACUAAGCCCUUUGGCCCUCAUUUUGUAAUCUAUAAGUGUGUGGGCCUAUUAUUUUAAUAUCCUGUCUACCUCUAACAAUUUCUGAUUGAAAUAUUGAAUUUGAAAAUAUAAAUAGGCAGUAUAAACUCUUCUGUUUAUCUGUGGCGUCUGUGAGGUAAUAAGCAGAAGAGGUUGAUAGUUUCACAAAAGGAAAGCAUGACUUAGACAGAGUGCCUAAAAUUCUGUCCCGGGAACCAUGAUCUCCUCAUCUACUGGCUGUCUGUGUUUGGGCAAUCACCUGCAUAUCAGUUUCCUCAUCUGCAAAAUGACAAUGGCACUUGCCAGCCACCACUUUUCAGGGCUCCUGAGCAGGUCAAAGACGUAACCUGCUCAAAUGUUUUGAAAACUAUUAAGUGCCAAUCAGAUUAUCAGUUGUCACUCAAAUUUGGAUUAAUUAGGUCAGAUAUUAGGUGUCAGGUGGUGUUUAAAUCCUUGUUGUCCAGAGUGACAUGGGAAGCACUGGAAGCUUAGGAUACCAUUAGGAGAUCCUGAGGCUUGAGUGAGAAGAUCCCAUAAAGAGCAACACGGCUCAAACAGCGCCAAGAGGGCAGGCUGUGUGCCAAGAUCAGCCUGGGAGUUUAUACAACACUUAUUUUAGCUUCAGACAUACUUUAGCCCCUAGAAAAGAAAGUGAACAGGAAGAGACCCUCGAGAUAUCUUUGGAUGCAUCAAGAAUUUUAAAAGCUGCAACUUGGAAUUCAAAGCAUUCACUUCCUUUUCCAACAAAAUUGAGACCCUAUAGGGUAAUUUUAUACUGAAGAGCUCCCAGUUCUUUAAACCUGAUUGGAAUUUGAGAUAGUUGGAACAGGACAAGACUCUUAUUACCUAUGAUAAAAGGCAUCAUCAGGUAGGGGCAAGAGUAUGGACUCUGGAGGUAGGUUGGAUUCAUAUCCCAGUUUUCAACAAUUUAUUUUGAGUCCCUUGGCAAAUCAUCUAGCAUCUCACCUCAGUUUUUUCAUCUAUAAAAUGAGAAGGAUGUAACACCUGCUUCAUCAGGUGGCGAUGAGGACAGAUGCGAGAAUACAGUGGAAUACUGAAUUCUGGUGACUUUCAAUAUUCUAUUCCUCAGCACUAACCCAUGCUUACAUGCAUUUUAUGACAAUCCACGUUACCUAAGCCCAAAUUAUUACCUGCAACGCAGCUUGGCAACCUUCAAACACUAACCAAAUCAGGUAUCAGAGCCCUUGUUUCUUGAACUUUCAAAGACAGAAGAUGAACAUAUAAAAUAGAAUAUUUUGUUUCAUGAUUUUGUUACUGUAAGCCAUGUCUGGUAAAGACCAAUACAAGGAAAAUGGGCUGAAUCUGUGAAUUACAUCAGCAGGUUCAGAAUAAAUGAUGGCUCACACACCAGAACUCAUUUCAAUCAUCCCUAAAUUUAAAACAGGAAAAUGGUUGGCAAAGUUGUUCCCUUUCUUCCUCUGGAGAAACUACUUGAAAUAAAUAUGAAUUUGAAUUUUACAUGAAUGAUAUCUCAAGAGUUUGUUAGUAUGAUUAUCAUACUUCAAGUUUAUGGCUUAUCCAGAAAUCAAACAACUAUAGUAACCAGAUAAAAGUCCUUUUUUUUUUCUGUAACAUAUAACAGUAAUUAGAGUUUUCUACUUGUGACCUUAAGGUGUGUUGUCAUGGUCUUGACAUUUCUGCAGAAGUAAACUAUUCAAUUCAGUAGUUUCUGUGUUUGCAGUUAUAUGUAUUUAACUUGUAUUUUGCAUAUUUAAUUUGUAUUUAAAUCGCUAAAAACUGGUAACUCAGAAAUGUUACGUAUAGACAUCCUCAUUUAUCCAGAAUAUUUGACUAACCAGACACCUAAUUAUGUUUUGAGUGGUCCUAUCUAUGCAUUUAAUGAAUGUUCUUAUUUUGUAGCCAGCAUAUGUAAUACAGGUGAUUCCUUUCAGCGAUGGGAGCUGGACAAAUCUAUAUGCAGGGUUUUUGAUCAUCUUGGGUUUAAAACUCAUAAUGGAGCAAUUAAAACCAUGUUUGUUUUCCUGAAUCCAUGACAACAAUAACUUUAUCCCAAAACCAGCUGUGAAUGUUGGUAACACGGGCACUCUGCUGACCUGAAGGAAUGCAGGCACAGUGCAUUUUGCACACAUGUUUGUCGGUAGAGUACUUUUUUGGUAGAGAGGAAGAGAAAAUUCUGGCUUCUUUAGAGAAGUGGAUGUAGGCAAUCCCUCCUCCAAAAGUAGUCAAAAUACCACUCCAGAGAACCUUGACUUUAUAAGGGAAGGCAGCUUCUGAAUCACUGAAAGCCUUUUCCUCCUUAAUUCUCACUGGCUGGCCUGGAAUGAGGCUCUGCUAAAAAUGUUAGAGGCAGCUGUUGAUAUAGGCAUUUCUGUCCUCUUUUCUAGUACCAUAAUGUGUGCAUGUUAAAGAGAUUCUGCAGGUCCCUUAUACCUUAUUCAUCCCUUUUAAAGCCUUCUUCUUGGAAAGUAGAUGUGGAGGAUCUAGAAUUGGAAAAGUUUCUGUCUUUCAGAACUUUGUGUAGGUUUGGUAUUCAUAAAACAUUACAUUAUUUGAUGUCUCCCCCCAACCCCCACCCCGCAAUACUACACAGAGAUGAAAAAUGUGUUUAGGUAGAAGAUCCUCCUAAAUAAGAAGGAAGGGUCUGGAAAGCUGUUAUCUGGGUUGUAUUACAACUUUGUGUUUUUUUCUCUCUUAUUAAAUAAUACUCAAGACAAACACUUUUAUAAGUAGGAUCUUGAUUAUUGAGGCAAGAAGUAUAAUCUUAAGCAGUGAGAAUGGGGGAAAUUGGAACACAUUGUUAUUCCCAUAGGAUCAGCAUAGAUUUCCGUAAUGUCCAAAUUACCUUGCCAUUUCUUUCAUUUCCCAAAAAAAGCUCUUUAGUGUCAAUUUUCCAUCAAAAAAAAAUCUUUGGAAGAAGUGAGUAUUUCCACAUUCUGCUAUGCCUUAGGGCAUCAGCUGUGCCCAAACUCAUGCUUGUAAGGCUGAAUGGUCACUCUGCUUUUGAUGUCUCUAUUUGAAAAAGCCUACAAAUCCAAAGAAAGCAUGCCCCCAUUGGCAUAGUCUCUGUUGUGCAAAGGAGACUUUCAGAGCUUUAGGCUCCAUCUGUCAUGAUCAUUUUUCAAACAGACUAUUUUUUAGAUCAGUUUUAUGUUUGCAGCAUCAAGAUCACUUUUUUUUUUGGCUGGUUUACUCCUACUCAAAUUGUUUCUGGCUCUCUGGGAUGACCAGUUUCUCAAGGAAAGAAACCUCCUCUGACCACCAUAUCAUCCUCCCAACUAUAUCUUUUCAUAUACGUUAAUAGCACUCUAUCUUUCCUUCAUAGUACUUACUGUAGUUUGUAGUAAUACAUUUGAUACAAUUAUUUCAUUCGUAUACAUCUUCCUCACCAGCCUAGGGAAGGGACACUGAUUGUUCACCAUCAUAUCCCAGUAUCUAGCACAGUGCCUAAGGGAUAGGAGGGGCUCAGUAAAUAUCUCUUGCAAGGAUGUUGUUAAAUUGUAAACUCUGCCAAGGCCUUUAUGUUGAAUGAAUGAAUGAACGAAUGAAUGAAUGCCUCUAACUCUUCAUAAAAUAAACACUUUUUGGAAAAAAUUGCUCAUGGCAGACGUCAGAUGUAACCACACUGAUAACUGGAAAGAAAAAUGAAUUUAGAUGGGUUUUAGAGAUAGAACAAUGUUUCUAAUAUUCAAGCAGUCCAUAAAUCCCUUAUACUUAAUGUUAAAAUUCAGGAUAUGAUACCUAAAGAAAGGUUUUACUGUACUUGGAUCAAGGCACCUACCAACUUUUUCUCUACUCAUAGGCAAAGUCACUACCCUGUUUAAGGAGGUCUUUGGACGUUUCCAUCUCAAGAAACAGCUCUUCAAUCUCUCCCUUGUAUUCCACCUUCCAGAACCACCCAGAAAUUCCAGUAAAGUCUUAUUGACCUGAUUGUCUGUCCUCUUCGCUGAGUUCCUUUUGAAUGCAGCAAAUUGCUGUGCCCUUUUCUGACUUCCAUUUCACUUUUAUCCAGCUUCAUAGGAGCUUAGGCCCCUGCUUGUUGAGGAGGGCGUUCAGUUAGUGCUGAGACUACCUGAAUAGGUCUGGUUCUAGCUACUCACAACUCAGAGAGGUAGUGAAUGCUAGGAGGUAGGAAGAAGGACAUUCAACCAGAAUACUAAAAUUGCAUUUAGAUAGUCCAGAAAUUAGACAGUUGGCACAGCAUUAGAAUUCCCCAUUUAUCCUUACAAUAGUUUGCUGAGAAUGAUGGUUGGGAAUUGAACAAUGAGAACACUUGGACACAGGAAGAGGAACAUCACACACCGGGGCCUGUUGUGGGGUGGGGAGAGCGGGGAGGGAUAGCAUUAGGAGAUAUACCUAAUGUAAAUGACAAGUUAAUGGGUACAGCACACCAACAUGGCACGUGUAUACAUAUGUAACAAACCUGCACGUUGUGCACAUGUACCCUAGAACUUAAAGUAUAAUAAAAAAGUGUGUGUGUGUGUGUGUGUGUGUAUAUAUAUAAAGAAUUCCCCACUUAAUAUUUAUACAUCCAAAAACUGACAAAAAUAAUGUCUGAACUCAUGUCUGACAUUCAGAUUCCUCCGCCCAAAGGCAAUAAAUAAAAUAAUACUAAGAUGUAAAGGCAAACCUUGUCUUCUGUCAUGAUCUACAGAUGGCACAAAUAAUAGACAUUUUCCCGAAUAAUGGCGUCUGAUUUUCAAGCAAUGCUUAGCCAAUUGUAGAUUUGGGCAGAAAAAGUUUGUACCAAGCAUUUGAGCUGGAAAAGGCAGAUAUUUUUCUUGACCUCACUUUUCCUAAAGUUCACAACUUCUGCUACUUAAAUGAGUAUCUCAUCUCUAAGUGUGUGAAGUAACAGAUGAUGUAUCUGUUUUUCAUCCUCAAAGAGUUAACUUGAUAAAAUAAGUACAGCUAAGGACAAACACAAACACAAAAUGAGAAAACUUCAUGCAGUAUGUUUUGUGUUUUGUAAAGGGUGCCAAUGGCAUGGAGCCAUCUGAUUCUGUUGCAGUCUUUGGCAACACGGCCCAUUUAAAUUCAAGUUAGGAUCUGAGUGUUUGGGUAAACAGAAUAAGCUAAGAAUGAGUGGCAGACAUAUUUCCUCAAAUCCCAUCUGAUACAGGUUUAGAUCCAGAUUUUGUCAUUUGACUAACUCCUUCCUUUUUUAGAUGAUUUGGAUUUGCCUUUUUUUCUUAUAAUAAAAGUCAUAAUGCCAACCACUUUAAGAGUUCUUUUGCUGCUCUUUUUUGUUGCUAUCUUUUUGUAACUAAUAGGACACGUGUAAGACUAUAAUACAAACAGGAGUCCUAGCAUGUAAUGGCUUUAGCAAUUUGUGCAAUAUCCCUCUUUUUGUCCUUCCUGCAUAUUUUCUCCCUAGAAAGCAGCCAAGAAUUGGUGUUCAGAGGGUGAUGCUCUGAUGGUGAGCAGAUCUACAGUUUGCCUAACAGUUUAUUUAAGCCAAAUUUAUAGUUUCUGAAGCGCUAGAAGGCUGCUGUCCAAGGGGACUACUUUUUUUUUUUUUUUUAGAUGGAGUCUUGCUCUGUCGCCAGGCUGGAGUGCAGAGGCGUGAUCUCAGCUCACUGCAACUUCUGCCUCCCCAGUUCAUGCUAUUCUCCUGCUUCAGUCUCCUAAGGAGCUGGGACUACAGGCUCACACCACCACGCCCAGUUAAUUUUUGUAUUUUUAGUAGAGACAGGGUUUCACCAUGUUGGCCAGGAUGGUCUCAAUCUCUUGACCUUGUGAUCCACCCGCCUCAGCCUCCCAAAGUGCUGAGAUUACAGGCAUGAGCCACCACGCCCAGCCAGGGACUACUUAUUAACUGGCCAUUUAAAAUGAAAUGAAACAAGGUCCUCAAUUGCUAACGAUUAAGGGGAGAGGAGUGUAAAUUCAGCUAUUGUCUUGUCUUCAGGCAGCAGGAAAUUAAGGGAUUGGUAACUGUUAUUUGUAAUAGUAAUUGAUGUCACAAAAGGAGUUUUGAGAACAGGGAGUUUAGGAAAAAAAUUGAUCUCCUUUUAUUUUUAGUCUGUUAAUAUUUAAUGUAAUAUUUGAUACAGUUCGAUUUAGAUUUACUGUUCUUUGAUCUAUUUUUAUUUUUUGCCUUUUUUGUUGUUCUCUUUCUUCUCUCCUGCCUUCUUUUAUAUUGUUUAAUUUUUUUUCUAAAUUUCAUUGUAAUUUAUCUAUUAGCUUUUUAACUAUAUCUUUUGGCAUUAUUUUUACAAAGUUGCUCUAGGGAUUACAAUAUACAUCCUUAAAUACUCACCAUCUACUUCAUGGAAAUUACUGUAACCUUACAAAUGUAUAAAUCGAUUUUACCCUUGUUCAUCCCAUUAUAAUGUAUAUUAUAAGCCUCAUACAAUGGUAUGAUUUUUACUUUUUCUCUGCGUUGUUUCUAGUUAACUAUAUGUGCUAUCAAAGUGAGACCCCAUUUAUCUUUUAAUCUGUUUCUGAUUGUUUUUCCAGUGUCUACUUAACUGAGACUCUUACAGGUAAUUUUGUAGGAUACUAGGUGUUUUAGAUGGCAAAUAUAAAGAUUGUGUUUGUGUAUGUGUAUGUGUUUAUAUGUGAGGGCCAAUCUAUUGAAAAGAAACACUGCAGAAUACUAAAGCAAAAUUGAAACCAUUUAGAGUUUGUAGUUGUUUUAUUUUAAAAGCUAACCUUGUAAGUACUUAGUCUUUCAAAAAAUAAUUUUAACUUCUAUGUUUUAUUUUUCUAUUUUAAUUUUUCCUGGGCCUUGCCUCCCAAUCCUCUCACCUUCCCUUUCUUCUGUGUGACCUAUAGAUUCAGAAAUUCCUUUCUGGGAUAAUUUCUGGCACUGCUUUGGAGAUGGAGCCCCUGAAAAUUGGCUAUGGACCAAAUGGAUUCCCACUCUUGGGGAUCUCUAGGUCAUCAUCACCAUCUGAACAGCUCUGAGAGAGACAAGAAGUGGAAUGGAGAAGGUGAUUAGAUGCUCAGAGUGUGUGCACAAGGCUGGCACGCCCAGGGUCUUCCUCAUGGCACUAACAGUCUACUGAAAGGUGGAACAGAGACAAGCCUAUCAACACCUACAAGACUGGUGGUUCUUACGUCUGUUGCUAGAUUAUCGUCCAAAAGUGUUAAUGCCCAAGUGACUGACAUCAACUCCAAGGGAUUGGAAUUGAGGAAGACUGUUACUACAGUUGAGACUCAGAACUUGGAAGGCCUGCAUCAUGAUGGCCAAUUCUGCCAUAAGCCCUGUCCUCCAGGUGAAAGGAAAGCUAGGGACUGCACAGUCAAUGGGGAUGAACCAGACUGCGUGCCCUGCCAAGAAGGGAAGGAGUACACAGACAAAGCCCAUUUUUCUUCCAAAUGCAGAAGAUGUAGAUUGUGUGAUGAAGGACAUGGCUUAGAAGUGGAAAUAAACUGCACCCGGACCCAGAAUACCAAGUGCAGAUGUAAACCAAACUUUUUUUGUAACUCUACUGUAUGUGAACACUGUGACCCUUGCACCAAAUGUGAACAUGGAAUCAUCAAGGAAUGCACACUCACCAGCAACACCAAGUGCAAAGAGGAAGGAUCCAGAUCUAACUUGGGGUGGCUUUGUCUUCUUCUUUUGCCAAUUCCACUAAUUGUUUGGGUGAAGAGAAAGGAAGUACAGAAAACAUGCAGAAAGCACAGAAAGGAAAACCAAGGUUCUCAUGAAUCUCCAACUUUAAAUCCUGAAACAGUGGCAAUAAAUUUAUCUGAUGUUGACUUGAGUAAAUAUAUCACCACUAUUGCUGGAGUCAUGACACUAAGUCAAGUUAAAGGCUUUGUUCGAAAGAAUGGUGUCAAUGAAGCCAAAAUAGAUGAGAUCAAGAAUGACAAUGUCCAAGACACAGCAGAACAGAAAGUUCAACUGCUUCGUAAUUGGCAUCAACUUCAUGGAAAGAAAGAAGCGUAUGACACAUUGAUUAAAGAUCUCAAAAAAGCCAAUCUUUGUACUCUUGCAGAGAAAAUUCAGACUAUCAUCCUCAAGGACAUUACUAGUGACUCAGAAAAUUCAAACUUCAGAAAUGAAAUCCAAAGCUUGGUCUAGAGUGAAAAACAACAAAUUCAGUUCUGAGUAUAUGCAAUUAGUGUUUGAAAAGAUUCUUAAUAGCUGGCUGUAAAUACUGCUUGGUUUUUUACUGGGUACAUUUUAUCAUUUAUUAGCGCUGAAGAGCCAACAUAUUUGUAGAUUUUUAAUAUCUCAUGAUUCUGCCUCCAAGGAUGUUUAAAAUCUAGUUGGGAAAACAAACUUCAUCAAGAGUAAAUGCAGUGGCAUGCUAAGUACCCAAAUAGGAGUGUAUGCAGAGGAUGAAAGAUUAAGAUUAUGCUCUGGCAUCUAACAUAUGAUUCUGUAGUAUGAAUGUAAUCAGUGUAUGUUAGUACAAAUGUCUAUCCACAGGCUAACCCCACUCUAUGAAUCAAUAGAAGAAGCUAUGACCUUUUGCUGAAAUAUCAGUUACUGAACAGGCAGGCCACUUUGCCUCUAAAUUACCUCUGAUAAUUCUAGAGAUUUUACCAUAUUUCUAAACUUUGUUUAUAACUCUGAGAAGAUCAUAUUUAUGUAAAGUAUAUGUAUUUGAGUGCAGAAUUUAAAUAAGGCUCUACCUCAAAGACCUUUGCACAGUUUAUUGGUGUCAUAUUAUACAAUAUUUCAAUUGUGAAUUCACAUAGAAAACAUUAAAUUAUAAUGUUUGACUAUUAUAUAUGUGUAUGCAUUUUACUGGCUCAAAACUACCUACUUCUUUCUCAGGCAUCAAAAGCAUUUUGAGCAGGAGAGUAUUACUAGAGCUUUGCCACCUCUCCAUUUUUGCCUUGGUGCUCAUCUUAAUGGCCUAAUGCACCCCCAAACAUGGAAAUAUCACCAAAAAAUACUUAAUAGUCCACCAAAAGGCAAGACUGCCCUUAGAAAUUCUAGCCUGGUUUGGAGAUACUAACUGCUCUCAGAGAAAGUAGCUUUGUGACAUGUCAUGAACCCAUGUUUGCAAUCAAAGAUGAUAAAAUAGAUUCUUAUUUUUCCCCCACCCCCGAAAAUGUUCAAUAAUGUCCCAUGUAAAACCUGCUACAAAUGGCAGCUUAUACAUAGCAAUGGUAAAAUCAUCAUCUGGAUUUAGGAAUUGCUCUUGUCAUACCCCCAAGUUUCUAAGAUUUAAGAUUCUCCUUACUACUAUCCUACGUUUAAAUAUCUUUGAAAGUUUGUAUUAAAUGUGAAUUUUAAGAAAUAAUAUUUAUAUUUCUGUAAAUGUAAACUGUGAAGAUAGUUAUAAACUGAAGCAGAUACCUGGAACCACCUAAAGAACUUCCAUUUAUGGAGGAUUUUUUUGCCCCUUGUGUUUGGAAUUAUAAAAUAUAGGUAAAAGUACGUAAUUAAAUAAUGUUUUUGGUAUUUCUGGUUUUCUCUUUUUUGGUAGGGGCUUGCUUUUUGGUUUUGUCUUCCUUUUCUCUAACUGAUGCUAAAUAUAACUUGUCUUUAAUGCUUCUUGGAUCCCUUAGAAGGUACUUCCUUUUUAACCUUAACCCUUUUAGUAGUUAAAUAAUUAUUUCCAUAGGUUGCUAUUGCCAAGAAGACCUCUUCCAAACAGCACAUGAUUAUUCGUCAAACAGUUUCGUAUUCCAGAUACUGGAAUGUGGAUAAGAAAGUAUACAUUUCAAGGGGUAGGUUUUAUUAUUAAGAAAGCCAAAUGAGGAUUUUGAAAUAUUCUUUCCUGCAUAUUAUCCAUUCUAGCUACAUGCUGGCCAGUGGGCCACCUUUCUUUUCUGCAAUUUAAUGCUAGUAAUAUAUUCUAUUUAACCCAUGAGUCCCAAAGUAUUAGCAUUUCAACAUGUAAGCAUGUCGGUAAGAUAGUUGUGCUUUGCUUAGGGUUCCCUCCUGUGUUAUGGUCUGGAAAGUGUCUUUAGGCAGAAAGUCUGAGUGAUCACAGGGUUCACUCAUUAAUUUCUCUUUUCUGAGCCAUCAUAGUCUGUGCUGUCUGCUCUCCAGUUUUCUAUUUCUAGACAGAAGUAGGGCAAGUUAGGUACUAGUUAUUCUUCAUGGCCAGAAGUGCAAGUUCUACUUUGCAAGACAAGAUUAAGUUAGAGAACACCCUAUUCCACUUUGGUGAACUCAGAGCAAGAACUUUGAGUUCCUUUGGGAGGAAGACAGUGGAGAAGUCUUUGUACUUGGUGAUGUGGUUUUUUUCCUCAUGGCUUCACCUAGUGGCCCCAAGCAUGACUUCUCCCAUGUCAAUGAGCACAGCCACAUUCCCGAGUUGAGGUGACCCCACGGUCCAGAAUCAUCCUCAUUCUGGUGAACCUGGUUCUCUUUGUGGUGGGCAUACUGGGUAGGAGAAUCACCCAAAGGUCACCCAUGAGCUGCAGAAAAAAAGGCUAUUUGCAGAAGGAGCUCACAGAUCACAUUGAAAGCAUUGCAUAUUCAAACAUCUUGGUCUUCUUUAUUGGCAUGCCCACAGGGUCUUCUGACCUCUGAUUAGAUCAGACACUUUUUAGAUAUUGAAUCAUCAGUUUCUGUACAACUAUCUGAAUAAGGUAUAUAAUCAAUGAAAUUUAGAAUUUUUUUCUAUGCUUACUCCUGAUUGGUAAUUUGUUUGGGUUUAGAAUUCUAUACAAGGCCAUUUGUAAUUUUCCUCAGCACUUUAAAAAUAUUAAACCAUGUUUUCUUAA